GAGAGCGCGCCGUGCCCGCGGAGAGAGCGCGGCGCGGGAGGCCGGCGGCCGGCCGGCUGCAUGGCGCGCUGCGAGAGGCUGCGCGGAGCGGCCCUGCGCGACGUGCUGGGCCGGGCGCAGGGGGUCCUGUUCGACUGUGACGGGGUGCUGUGGAACGGCGAGCGCGCCGUGCCGGGCGCCCCGGAGCUGCUGGAGCGGCUGGCGCGGGCCGGCAAGGCGGCUCUGUUUGUGAGCAACAACAGCCGGCGCGCGCGGCCCGAGCUGGCCCUGCGCUUCGCGCGCCUCGGCUUCGGGGGGCUGCGCGCCGAGCAGCUCUUCAGCUCCGCGCUGUGCGCCGCGCGCCUGCUGCGCCAGCGCCUGCCCGGGCCUCCGGACGCGCCGGGCGCCGUGUUCGUGCUGGGCGGCGAGGGGCUGCGCGCCGAGCUGCGCGCCGCGGGGCUGCGCCUGGCCGGGGACCCGAGCGCGGGGGACGGCGCGGCCCCGCGCGUGCGCGCCGUGCUUGUGGGCUACGACGAGCACUUCUCCUUCGCCAAGCUGAGGGAGGCGUGCGCGCACCUGCGCGACCCCGAGUGCCUACUCGUGGCCACCGACCGUGACCCAUGGCACCCGCUGAGCGACGGCAGCCGGACCCCUGGCACCGGGAGCCUGGCCGCUGCAGUGGAGACAGCCUCGGGACGCCAGGCCCUGGUGGUGGGCAAGCCCAGCCCCUACAUGUUCGAGUGCAUCACGGAGAACUUCAGCAUCGACCCCGCACGCACGCUUAUGGUGGGUGACCGCCUGGAGACCGACAUCCUCUUUGGCCACCGCUGCGGCAUGACCACUGUGCUCACGCUCACAGGAGUCUCCCGCCUAGAAGAGGCCCAGGCCUACCUAGCGGCCGGCCAGCACGACCUCGUGCCCCAUUACUAUGUGGAGAGCAUCGCAGACUUGACAGAGGGGUUGGAGGACUGAGCCCACUGCACCUGCAGCCACAGGCCCACCCCUCCCCACUCCCUGAUCCCGUAGGUGGAGGCGAUGGGUCACGAGCCAUGUUAAGCACAACCGGCUCCUUGGUCCAGUUCUGCACCGGGGUGGGGCUGGGACCCGGGGAAGGUUUGAGGGCCCUUGCAACCCCCUCCCAGCAGUGGCUGGGCACUCUUUGCUGCCCCAGAAGCUGGUCCCCUAUGGAUUCAUCUUGGCCUGACCCAGCCAGGUGGCCUUAUUUCUUCCCUGUCACCUCCCCUCCUUGAAAUCUGGGCCCUGGUGCCUGCUGAAGAUUCCCUCUAUCCCUGAGUACUUAGUCUUCUCCCCCUUCCCUGGGGCUUCUAGAGCUCUCUCUGCCCCUCAGGUCCUGGCCCUUGGGUCCUUGUCAACCAGAGGUCUAGGGAACCACAACCCUUAUUGUCCUGGGUGGACCAAUCCAAAGGCUAAGUGAUAGUGACUCAUCAAUGUUGGGUCCUGUGGGGUACCAGUUUAGGUUCCUAAGUAAUAGUGACCCUUUCACGUCCUGGAGCCCGAGUGGACCAAUCGGAAGCCUAAGUGACGAUGACCCUCGCAUGUCCUAGGUCCCUGGGUGGACCCAUCAGGACCCCAAGUGAUAGUGACCCAGUGGUCUUUUAGAUCCUCAGUAGAACAGUCCAGAAGCCUGAGAGACAGUGGCCCCUUGAUAAUCUGGGUCUCACGGGACCAGCUAGGGGUCCAGGUUUCAGUCAGUAAAUAAGAGUGGUCCACGUCCUAAAGACACCUCUCCUUUACAAAGACUUGUGAUGCUCUGGGGCUUCUGUGGCCAAGCCCCACCCUUUCCUGGUCAUGGUACCCGUACAGCGUUGAUGGCCACAGCUCGAAGGGGGGCUUUCGUGUCCCCCUGUGCGGUCAGUGUUUUCAGUACCACCUCUCUCCCGUGCCCACUUGGCUAUUUACUUAUUUAUUUAUUGUGUGCCAGUGAUGGUGGGUGGGGGCUGGGCCUUCCCCGCCACCUCCACCCCUGUUGUGACCUGUCCUUCCGUACUUAAUAAAGUGCGCGUGGGAGUGUU